CGGCGGCGAGAGGGGACGGGACGCGUCCUGGCGCUCGGCGGUCCGUUCGUCCGAGCGUGACCGCUGUGGGGAGGUCAGGGCUGGGCGGGAUUUACUCCGUGCCAAUAUCCCCACUCCCGAACUUCUUCUUGUCAAAGCAUCCCAACUCCGCCCGGGACGCGGUUCCAGUCCGCACCAACUUGGCGUAAUUGACAUGGGUAGGUGGGGCCGGGACGCGUCCCCUGCCCCUCUGCGGCAACGACAUGGAGCGCUGGGGCGGCCUCCGCGCCCGCGGCGUGCGGACCGCGGUUCCUGAAAAAUUACCCGCGCUGUGCGGUACGGUAAGACCCGGCGUCCGCGUCUGGAUCUCAAGGCUGAGCGAGCGCUCAUCGGGCUCAAGAUGGAAAUCCUGUAUGAAUGUGGAAGCCAUUAGCAGAGUAAUUGCUGUCUGUUACCAUGACAACCAGCCGCUGCAGUCACCUGCCCGAAGUCCUGCCAGACUGCACCAGCUCAGCUGCACCCGUGGUGAAGACGGUGGAGGAUUGUGGCAGCCUAGUGAAUGGGCAGCCGCAGUAUGUCAUGCAAGUUUCAGCCAAGGACGGGCAGCUGCUGUCAACAGUAGUGCGGACUCUUGCCACCCAGAGCCCCUUCAAUGACCGGCCGAUGUGCAGGAUCUGCCACGAGGGCAGCAGCCAAGAGGACUUGCUCUCUCCAUGUGAAUGUACAGGGACCUUGGGGACAAUUCAUCGGAGCUGCCUGGAGCACUGGCUGUCAUCCUCAAACACCAGCUACUGUGAACUCUGCCACUUCAGGUUUGCAGUCGAGCGCAAACCCAGGCCGUUAGUGGAGGUGCAGCAGAUUUGGGGGAAGAUAAGAAAACACCCCUGUCAGGUCUUCAGGCUUUGCCGUCCUCCUCAUUCUUCAUGGAAUUGGCUGAGAAACCCUGGCCCCCAGCAUGAGAAGCGGACUCUGUUUGGCGACAUGGUGUGCUUCUUGUUUAUAACUCCCCUGGCCACCAUCUCGGGCUGGCUGUGCCUGCGGGGCGCCGUGGACCACCUGCACUUUAGUAGUCGGCUGGAAGCCGUCGGACUGAUUGCACUCACUGUCGCACUCUUCACUAUUUACCUCUUUUGGACACUAGUGUCAUUUAGGUACCACUGUCGAUUGUACAACGAGUGGCGUCGGACCAAUCAGAGGGUGAUUCUCCUCAUUCCAAAGUCUGUCAAUGUACCUUCUAACCAGCCGUCCUUGCUGGGCCUCCAUUCGGUCAAGAGGAACUCAAAGGAGACAGUUGUUUGAUGUUUGUAUGGUUGGUUGGUUGUUUGAUUCAUUGUUUGGGGUUUGGAAGUGUCUGCACUGGGGUCAUGCACUGAGCGACCCCCAAGCCCUUCCUUAAGCCUGUGGGUCUAAGAACAUCCAGAGCAUAUUAGCACAUCACUCCAAGCAACAACCUCCGCCAGAAGAAAGCAAAUGCUGUUUUACUUCAAAUGAUGGAUGCUGCAAUCAUAUGAUAUUUGCUAAGCUGCCAAACAUGUUUAUUUAGCAGAUACUGUAUGGAAUUUUCUGAACACCUCUUUAACGUAUGAGGAAGGUUGUCCUGCUACGGAUGCAAUUCAAUUCUUCCUUUUUUAUUACUAUUUCAAACACACACACAUAUAUAUAUAUAUUAAACUUAGAUGAUAAUCAAAAUCAAAAAGUCAACGUAAAAACUGGUUUCUUGGUUUGGUUGGGUCUUAUUUGAGUUAGUUUGUUUCUCAGUUUCUCGUAUGGAUUCUUUGGGGUACUUUGGUAGCCUGAGUGGUCUUUUUCAUCUCUUUCGCGUCCAUUACUCAAGGAGACAGCAUAACAGAUGCAGAACAAGUCAUAUUUGAAGAAUGUUUUGUACUAAACUUCAUUUAAUUAUUCAGUUUUUAAAGGGAAAAAGGGCGUGAGCUCACACAGUGAGCUGUUUAUUUAAAUAUCAUUAAGGAGAAAAAAAAAUAUGGUGAGAAGCUCGCUCCUUUCAACUUGUUUGGUACUGACAGCUGAUAGAAGCUAUUUUCUAAUAAUAAACAUCCAGUGUGUGAAAGACAAAACCCACUGAUUGCAAUACUCUUUUUUUAAUGAUAAAACCUGUGAAGUUUCCCAAAGCAGGUUUUAAAAGGAAAAAAAGGAAAAGCAAAAAGGUUGCUGUUCUCACUCCCAUCUCAUUUAGUGCAUGUCUUAAUUCGGGAUUCGUAAUGAAUUGGAGGAUCAUUAGACAUUUCUAGGAACCCUAGACCUGUUUUGCAUGUCAAUUAGCAUUCCCAUUGCUCUAUUGAAUUUCUAGCUUGACAGGUAGAUGUGGCAAAAAAAAAAAAAAAAAAAAAAGCCUGUCCUAGCAGCCCUGCACUUAUUCUAAGACCCCUUUGUCUGAUUCUUUAAAAAGGAGCCCCACACAGUGCCUUCCCCCAACCAUGAGCCAAUUCUGUCACAGUCCGAAAUAGACUUUUUCUAAGGGUUUCGUGUCCCUCUUUUAUCCGUCGCAGUGUAAAGGGUCUGAUCCGCAGCCUGCAUUGUGCGCGCACCGAGGCAGGAGCGGAUGUCUUCUGAGGAGAGCGCUGGCUGGGGUUGACUCUCAGGCUCCCGGCUGUCCGCCCGCCCACACGCAGCGAGGAGGGGCGGAGCCCUGCUUCCGGAAUGCUUAAAAUAUGGAAUUCUAGAACAUGACCCACAUUCUGAGUAUCACUCCAGCAUCUGCCUUGUGUUCCAAGUGGGAAAACGAGAAGUGCAAAGGAACAGGCAGCGAGGAGGGUAGCGAUUUUUGUCUGCAAAUUGAUGGAGCUGAUGCAGGUGUCCCCUUUGUAGGCGAGCCCUCCAUUCACUGGCUGCUCCCAGCGCUGCCUGGGGAGGGAAACAGCUGUACUGCUCUCCGCUGCAAAACUCAGAUGUGCUUUAUGGCUUGUGACAAUAGAUUUCCUCCCCACCACGCUUCACUGGGACACUUCAAUUCCAGUAAUAUAUGUCUCAGCCCUUCUGUUUACUGCGCCCUGCUCACCCCCCUGGGCUGUCAUUAGCUGCACCACCAUCAACCGUUUCUUAAUUGACCUUUUUAAAAUGCUGGACAUCACCGGCUGCACGCAGCUGCCACACAUUAAAUUUCCAGAGCAAAGAGUCCAACUUGGUAGCUGGUGAAUUGCAGCCCUGUAAUAUACUUAAUAAAUGACGUCCACCCAGCCUUAGUCCCUGAGCUGUCAGGUGAACCCGUGACACGUCUCAACUGAAUGGCACAACAUUCAUGAGAGGACCAUACCCCUUCUCCCUGUUUCUUGCAUGAAUUAAGGAAGCAGCGGAUUUCCAGGAUGAUUUCCUGUCAAGGUUGGCUGCAGAGAAUUCCUGCCAUCUUGGUUCAUGAGAUGAGAUAUGACAUCAUCAAAGGCAGCCAGGUCCCAGGCCGUUCAAUGGGGAUCCUGCAUUAGGAAGGGUUUGCACAUUAAAACUGUGCCUGUGCCACACCUCUUUCCUUCGUGUUUGCAUCCCUGCCCUGUGAAGUAAAACAGAGUCCAAGAUGCAAGGAGUAGAUUGUGUGUGGGGUGGUGAAAGGACACCCCUGGCAGCCAGGCAGAGCAUCAGUGCCUCCCUUCCCAGGUCACCAGCUUGGGACCUCCUUGUGAGAGGCUCUGAUCUCCAUCAGCAUCAGGGCCCAUAGGGGAUUCUGAACUCUUGGAGGAUAUUUCAUCCCCUCCAAGCCUUGCCCCAUGGAAAGGGCUACACCUCCUGCAGGAAGGGGUGCCUUUUGUUAACAGGUAUUAAUGGGUACAGAGGCACCAUGCAGCCUACCAGCACCCUUGCUAGCCUAGUCCUCUUCCUGUGCUUCUUUUUGAAAGAUCAAGAAUGAAGAGGAAGAGAUGAGGAGUGGGGGUCCUUUACCUAAAGGACCCUCGUGGUUCAUUGCUUCUCUUUAACUGACUUUUUAAAAAAACUCCCUCUUCCACACUCCUUGCUGUGAUUCUGUCCUAAUCAUUUUUCUUGAGAAUGUCAUGUAGAGAUAAAUGUGUGUCACAGUGAAGCCAGAAGGUGAAUUAACAACUAAGACAAAUCCAGCAUGCUCUUGCCUGCCCUGCAUAUGUGCUCAUUUGGGGAAGGACGGAGGACACAGAGCAUCGACACAAAUUCUACAGCUCCUCAGAGAACACAGCAGAGACUCAGAUGAGCUGUAAAAUCCAUUAAGGAAAAAUAAAUGGCAUGAUUUGGAAGUUA